AAAUUGUUUUACAGCCUACCCGUAUAUUACAAGAAAUCUCAAGUCAAACACUGGAAAAGAUGUCAGAAGAUUCAGAAAAGGAAGACUAUUCAGACAGAACAAUCAGUGAUGAAGAUGAAUCGGAUGAGGAUAUGUUCAUGAAAUUUGUAAGUGAAGAUCUUCAUCGGUGUGCACUUUUAACAGCUGACUCUUUUGGUGAUCCCUUCUUCCCCCGGACUACACAGAUACUAUUAGAAUAUCAGCUAGGGAGAUGGGUGCCACGUCUUCGUGAACCAAGGGAUUUAUAUGGUGUCUCUUCUUCUGGUCCAUUGAGCCCAACACGGUGGCCAUACCAUUGUGAAGUCAUCGAUGAAAAAGUCCAGCAUAUUGAUUGGACUCCUUCUUGUCCUGAGCCAGUGUAUAUCCCAACGGGCUUAGAAACGGAACCCCUUUAUCCAGACUCCAAGGAAGCUACUGUGGUUUAUCUAGCUGAAGAUGCUUACAAAGAGCCCUGUUUUGUGUAUUCCCGAGUUGGGGGUAACCGAACACCUUUGAAGCAGCCUGUGGAUUACCGUGACAAUACUUUGAUGUUUGAAGCAAGGUUUGAGAGUGGUAAUCUACAGAAGGUAGUCAAAGUGGCAGAAUACGAAUACCAAUUGACUGUACGCCCUGACCUCUUCACAAAUAAACACACCCAGUGGUACUAUUUCCAAGUCACUAAUAUGCGAGCAGGAAUAGUCUACAGAUUCACUAUUGUCAACUUCACCAAACCUGCUAGUCUUUACAGUCGGGGUAUGCGCCCACUGUUCUAUUCUGAAAAAGAGGCCAAGGCUCAUCACAUUGGCUGGCAGAGAAUAGGAGACCAAAUCAAGUAUUAUAGGAACAACCCAGGCCAAGAUGGGCGCCAUUAUUUCUCUCUUACAUGGACAUUUCAAUUUCCACACAACAAAGAUACCUGCUACUUUGCUCAUUGCUAUCCAUACACUUACACCAACCUGCAAGAAUACCUUUCUGGCAUCAAUAAUGAUCCAGUACGGUCAAAGUUUUGUAAAAUACGUGUUUUGUGCCACACGCUUGCUAGGAACAUGGUGUAUAUUUUAACAAUCACUACCCCCUUGAAGAACUCUGACUCAAGAAAGCGGAAGGCUGUGAUUCUGACUGCAAGGGUCCAUCCAGGGGAAACCAACAGCUCUUGGAUCAUGAAAGGCUUCCUAGAUUAUAUUUUAGGAAACUCAAGUGAUGCACAGUUGCUUCGGGACACUUUUGUCUUCAAGGUGGUACCCAUGCUCAAUCCAGAUGGUGUGAUUGUGGGAAAUUAUCGCUGUUCCUUAGCUGGACGGGAUUUAAACCGUAAUUAUACAUCUCUCCUGAAGGAAUCUUUUCCUUCUGUAUGGUAUACCCGGAACAUGGUUCAUAGACUGAUGGAGAAACGAGAGGUUAUUUUAUACUGUGAUCUUCAUGGCCAUAGUAGGAAAGAGAACAUCUUCAUGUAUGGCUGUGAUGGUAGUGACAGAUCUAAGACAUUAUACUUACAGCAACGAAUCUUCCCACUUAUGCUAAGCAAAAAUUGUCCAGAUAAAUUUUCAUUCUCAGCUUGCAAGUUUAAUGUCCAGAAGAGCAAAGAAGGAACAGGAAGGGUGGUAAUGUGGAAAAUGGGAAUCAGGAACAGCUUUACCAUGGAGGCCACCUUCUGUGGAUCUACUCUGGGUAACAAACGAGGCACUCAUUUCAGCACGAAAGACCUGGAAUCAAUGGGAUAUCAUUUUUGUGAUUCUCUCUUGGAUUAUUGUGAUCCCGACCGGACCAAGAAAAAACAUUUGAAAACAAAGAAGGAAAGGAAUUCUACCAUAGCAAGCCACCAAAAUGCCAGAGGACAAGAGGUUUAUGAUAGAGGGCAUUUGCUGCAAAGACACACACAAUCAAAUUCUGAUGUGAAAGAUACAAGGCCAAAUGAACCAGAUGAUUAUAUGGUUGAUUAUUUCAGAAGACAAUUACCUAAUCAAGGUUUGGAUCUGCACCACAACUUAAAAAGCAAAAUAAAAGAAUGCAUAUCUUUCCAAAGCAAGAAGACUGGCAUAAAUUGGACAGAUGAUGAAAAAAGAAGCUACAAGGAUAAAGGAAUAGUUCAAACUCAAGAAAUAUUGCAGUAUUUGCUCCCCAUCGUGCAUAGCACUAAAAACAUGCAAACCACUCAGAUAAAACAGCUAUUCAAUCCAAGAACCAACUUCCAAAUCCAACAUCAAAUUUUCAUCAUUACCAAAUGGAAUGCCAAGCAUGAGAUUUAUUCCUCCAUAUUGAAAUCUGACCUAUGUUUGACCAGAGAGAAAUUUAAGGUAUGUAAAUCAUCUUGUUAACAUGCAAUUCACCUAUUAAUCCACCUAGACCCUAUUCAUUUUGGCUUAAGAACAGAACAGACAAUGUAGGUUUCAGCCCUAUGAUUACAUUCAGAUGUAACGUCAUGUUCAACAUGAUAAUUCUGCAAACUCUUACAGCACAUUAACUAGUUUCUCCUUAAUCCUAAAUUAGACCAAUGUCUAAAAUGGUUUAGCAAAGUGUGAUCUUCUCAUUCUUUGCUUAUUCUCACUUUACCCUGAAAUCACUUACUAUAGGUAAUAGCAUGUAAGAGUGUUGAGACAGUCAAACAAAUGAUAUAUAAAACAGAGAAGGUAGCCAUAAAGAACUAAGUUGUAAGAAAAACAACAACAACAAAAAUCAACCUGACAAUGUUUAAGUUUGCAGUGAGAUCAUCUGUUAAGAAAGGAUUUGCUUGCUGCUUUCCUACUUUUUAAUAUUUCCAUAUACACCUAUAUCAGAUACUUUUGGGGGUGUCUACCUCAGGCACAAUUUGCCCUUCUCUGGGGACUGCCUCUUGAUCCACAAGGGUAGCACUUCCAAAAGCUGCAUUUGUAAUUAUGUGACCUCUACCCACUGGCAUGGUUGCCAAUCAGAUUAUCUUUCUCUAUACUUUGGAAUUGGAAUGAGAGAUAGUGGAUCAGUCUUGCACAUGAAACUGCUGUAGGAUGCAAAUUUGAGCUAAGGGAAGUAAAAACUUUCCUGUGGAGAGAGAAAAGCAGAGACUGCAGAUGAAUAAAAACCCUUGGAUGUUUUCCAUUUUCUAGUUCUAGUCCUUUCCUGAAGCCUGGCUGAAUUCCCUCUCCCUCUGUUUCCAUGAGUAGCUUUGUACUUUCUUAUAAUUCUUCCCCUACCCUACCUUAUGCUUUUUUUAAUUAAGCUAGCUUGAAUUGGUUUCUGUUACUUGUAACCAAAGAGGUCUUAGUUAAUACCUCACUAUUUGUCUGUACCUUCAUGCUCAGGCCAAUCCUCAUUGAGUGCAUUUCUAGAUUCAAAGUAUUAAUAUAUAAGGAACCUCUUAUGAAAGUAAUGACUAAAAAUCACGCCAUGUCCUAAUUGUCACCUAGACCCCACCCCAAUCUCAAUGGAGGCUACAUAUGGAGAUGAACCUCCACAUCUGUCCAAUAAUAAUUAGAAGCCUCCUAUCUCUGGUGUCAAUGGGGUCCAGAUGGGGAACCUGGACUUCCACUUCCAUCUUGCAGUAAUGAGGUCUUAUCUCCCCACUCCCUGAGCUGGAGCAAACUAACAAAAAGCCAAAACAGAGGGUUUACAUAAGAUCCAGAGUCUCAUAACAUAAUAUGAAAGUGUCUAUGUUUUAAUCAGAAAUAAAUUCUUGUACCAAGAACCAGGAAGAUCUAAAACUGAAAAAAGACAAUUAGUAGACACAAACACUGAGAUGUUAAUGAUGUUAGAAUUUUUUGACAAAGAUUUUUAAAGUAAUCAUAAUUAAAAUGCUUCAAAAAACACUUAUAAACACACUUGGAAGAAAUAAAAAAAUAGCCUCAGCAGAGAGAGAGAGAAAAAAAUAUUAAGAACCAAAUAGAAAUUUUUGAAUUGAAAAAUACCACUGAAAUUUUAAAAGCUUAAUGGCUGAGCAGAACAGUAUAAUUGUACAAAUAGAGGAAAGAGUCAGUGAAUUGAGAGAGAUAGAAAAAUAGAAAUUACCCAACUGAACAUAAGAGAAAAAAUAGGCUUAAAAUAAAAUGAAUAGAGCUGCAGGCACCUGUAGGACUAUAAGACAAAAUCUAAUAAUAUUCACAUAUCGUAGUUUCAGAAGGACAGGAGAAUGAAUAUAGGGCUGAAAAAGAAAUCAAAGAAAUAAUGGCUGAAAGGUUCCCAAAUUUGACAGGAGACAUAAACCUAUAGAUCAAAAAGCUGAGCAGACCAUUAAUAGGAUACACCCAAAGAAAUUCAUGCCAAGAUACCCCAAAAUUUAAAUUUUUUUUUUUUUGAGACAAAGUCUUGCUCAGUUACCCAGGCUGGAGUCCAGUGGAACAAUCUUAGCUCACUGAAACCUCCGCCUCCUGGGUUCAAGUGAUUCUCGUGCCUCAGCCUUCCGAGUAGCUGGGGUUAUAGGCACCCACCACCAUGCCUGGCCCAAUUUUUGUAUUUUUAGUAGAGACGAGGUUUUGCUGUGUUGGCCAUGCUGGUCUCGAACUCCUGACCUCAAGUGAUCUGACUCCCUCAGCUCCCAAAGUGCUGGGAUUACAGGCAUGAGCCACCAUGCCCAUUCCCCAAAAUUUAACUUCUGAAAAUGAGACCAAAAAAAAAAGAAAAAACUAUCGAAAGGAGUCAGAGAGGCUGGGCACAGUGGCUCAUGCCUGUAAUCCCAGCACUUUGGGAGGCCGAGGUGGGCAGAUCACGAGUUCAGGAGAUCAAGACCAACCUGGCUAACACGGUGAAACCCCGUCUCUACUAAAAAUACAAAAAAUUAGCUGGGCGUGGCAGCGGGUGCCUGUAGUUCCAGCUACUCUGGAGGCUGAGGCAGGAGAAUGGCAUGAACCUGGGAGGCAGAGCUUGCAGUGAGCCAAGAUCGUGCCACUGCACUCCAGCCUGGGUGACAGAGCGAGACUCCGUCUCAAAAAAUAAAAAAAGAAAAAGAAAGGAGUCAGAGAAAAAUGACACCUUUCCUACAGAGGAAAAACAAUUUGAAUGACAGUGGAUUUCUCAUCAAAACCCACAAAGCACAAUAAUUUUAAUUAUUGGAAGAAAUUGUCAACUUAGAAUCCUAUACCCAGUGAAAAUAAGGGAGAAGUCAAGAAAGGUUCAGAUAAAAGAAAAUGAAGAGAAUUUUUCACCAGAAGACUUACUCUAAAAGAAUGACUAAAGGAAUUUUUCUAAACAGAUAGAAAAUGACAAAAGAAGGAAUAUCAGGAAAGAAAGAAUACGGUAAGCAAAAAUACAGGUAGAUAUAAAAUACACGUAAAUAUAAAUUUUUCUAAAUCAUAUUUGAUGGUUGAAGCAAAAAUUAUAAUAUUGAUGUGGUUCCAAAUAUACAUAAAAGACAUAUUUAAGACCACUAUAAAUGUGAGAAGGUAAAAGGACAUAAAAGGAGGUAAGGUUUGUACUUCACUCAAAUUACUAAGUUAACACAACCAAUAAAUUGUGAUAAGUUAUGCAUAUGUAGUAUAAUACAGCAACCACUGAAAAAGCUGUUCAAAGAGAUAUACUAAAAAACACUAAAUAAAUCAAAAUGGAAUUCUUGAAAAAUGUUCACAUUACCCACAGGAAGGCAGGAAAGAGAAAACAAAAAACAAAAGAUAAACUUUUUUUAAAUGGCAGAUUUAAGUCCUAAGACAUCAACUAUUACAUUAAAUGUAAAUGACCUAAAUACAACAGUUAAGGACAGAUUAACAGAAUGAAUUUUAAAACAUUACCCAACAAUAUGCAGUCACAAGAAACUCAUUUCAAAUAUGACAAUGGAGGCAGGCUGAAAGUAAAAGGAUGGAAGAAGAUACAUCAUGCAAACAUUAAUAGAUGAAAGCAGAAGUGGCUAUGUUAAUAUUAGGUAAAGUAGAUUUUAGAGGAAAGAAAAUUAUCAAAGAGGGGCAUUAUAUAUAAUGUUUAAAAGGUCAAUCCACUAGAAACACAGCAAUCUUAGAUGUGUGUAUAAAAUCACAGAACUGGCUGGGUGCAGUGGCUUACACCUGUAAUCCCAGCACCUUGGGAGGCCGAGGCAGGU